AGACGCAGAGGCGAGGCCGCCAGUCGAGGACGAGGAGGAGAUAACAUCAAGAUGCCGAAGACUGAGGAAACUGUGCUCCAGAAUGAUCCCAGUGUAGCAGAGAAUGGGGCCCCUGAGCCUAAAACACCAGGGCAGAGCCAGAAAAGCAAGAGUUUCUGUUUAGAUGACCAGUCUCCUGAUCUGAUAGAGACAGUUAAUGAAGUUUCCAAGCUGAGCAUUUCACAUGAAAUUGUAGUAAACCAAGAUUUCUAUGUGGAAGAGACCAUUUUGCCUCCAAACAGUGUAGAAGGCAGGUUUGCGGAGGCAAUGUACAAUGCUUUUUGGAACCAUCUGAAAGAACAGCUAUUGAGUACUCCUCCUGACUUCACUUGUGCCCUUGAACUUCUAAAAGAUGUUAAGGAGACCUUGCUAUCACUGCUAUUACCAUGGCAGAACCGCCUAAGAAAUGAGAUAGAAGAAGCUCUGGACACAGAUCUCCUCAAGCAGGAAGCAGAACAUGGGGCCCUGGAUGUCCCUCAUCUUUCUAACUACAUUCUCAAUUUGAUGGCUCUGCUAUGUGCACCGGUUCGAGAUGAAGCGAUACAGAAACUAGAGACCAUAAGAGAUCCAGUGCAGUUACUGAGGGGCAUCCUCCGUGUUCUGGGCCUAAUGAAAAUGGACAUGGUGAACUAUACCAUCCAGAGCUUUCGACCCUACCUGCAGGAACAUUCCAUCCAGUAUGAACAAGCUAAAUUCCAGGAACUCCUUGAUAAACAGCCCAGUCUCCUCGAUUAUACCACAAAAUGGCUAACCAAAGCAGCCACAGACAUCACUACACUAUGUCCGAGUUCUCCUGACUCACCUAGCUCCUCCUGCAGCAUGGUGUGUUCACUUCCAAGCGGGGCAGGUAACAAUUCAGAGCCCCCCAGUCCAACAAUGGUGCUAUACCAAGGUUACCUGAACCUCCUCCUCUGGGAUCUUGAAAACGUAGAAUUCCCAGAGACUCUGCUGAUGGACAGAAUCCGGCUCCAGGAACUGGCAUUCCAGUUGCACCAGUUAACUGUCCUGGCCUCAGUCUUGCUAGUGGCCAGAAGCUUCUCUGGUGAAGUUUUAUUCAGAUCACCUGAAUUUGUGGAUAGACUGAAAUGCACCACCAAGGCCCUAACUGAGGAAUUUAUCUCCAGGCCUGAAGAGACUAUGCUGAGUGUGAGUGAACAGGUGUCUCAGGAAGUCCAUCAAGGCCUUAAGGACAUGGGCCUCACUACUCUGAGCAGUGAAAACACAGCAUCUCUUCUAGGCCAACUCCAGAACAUCACCAAGAAAGAGAACUGCAUUCGUAGCAUUGUUGAUCAGUGGAUCCGUUUUUUUCUCAAAUGCUGUUUGCUUCAUGGCAUGCAGGAGUCUCUGCUACACUUUCCUGGAGGCCUCAUUCUCAUUGAAAAGGAGUUGGCAGAACUGGGCUGGAAGUUUCUCAAUCUGAUGCAUCAUAAUCAGCAGGUAUUUGGCCCAUACUAUGCUGAGAUCCUAAAACACAUCAUCCAUCCAGCUCAAGCACAAGAAACAGAUGUGGAGCCUAACUGAUAGUGCUGGACCCCAGCUAUGGCAACAGGGACUCAGGAGAGAGAGGUCAGCAUGUUUCUGGGAGGACAUCACCUGUGGUUAGUCGAACAGUCAGCCCUCUUCCUCGCUAUAGCCAGGACACAGGGAUGCAGGGGUCAAGCAUGUAAGCACCAACUGGCCCAAUCCCCUUCACUAAUAAACCUCUGAGCUGCAAGAAAA